GAUCUCUGGCAUUAAAGCAUCACACAGAAUGUUUCUCUUAUUCGAGCUCCUCUUUCCUCCACAUACAGGGAAUCAACAGACUAUUUUAUACGGUCUUUGGACUUUGCUUCUUUAUUUCCACCCUCUUUCAUAAAAAAAAAAGAAAAAGAAAAAAGAUACCGUGCUCCAUUUGCAUUUGAUCUUCCAAAAGGAAGGUACUGAUAAAACCGGAAUUUCAGCGAUACAGACGCAGGUCAACCGCUAAACAGUGAAGGCCAAGAGUCCCGCGCUGCAAGCCCAUAGCCGGCAGAGGGCAAUGGAACUCGCUUUCUGGUCGUGCGGGGCGCAUGCGCAUUCUGCUUGCGGAAGCGGGGCCAGAUCGCCAAGGAAGAAGGGAACUUCCCUUCCUCAGGCCAGGGAGGAGGAGGCGCCGCCCUGGCUUUGGGGCAAAUGGGGCUGCAUCCAUCUUAAGGAAAACGCUGCUGUUCACAGCCCUACCUGAUGAGGAGUGAGAUUCCCUGCGCGUCUCCCGGAUAUUUUUCUGAAACAGCACUAAAGACUUAAUGUUCUGGGCUGUUCCUACGUGUUUUCUUCUGCACUGUCUGUUGGGAUAUAUUAGCAAGAAUUAUUUUACAAAUCUACGUAUUCCUUAGGGAUUUUCAUUGAUAACCAUAGCAGGCCGUAAUGUGCCUUCCUCGCAACCUCUGUCAGGAUUCAUUAUGAGGAGAAACACAAGAAGAAUUGUGAGGAAAAUCUACAGAAUACGGGGACCCUGCAGAGGAAGGAGUAUGUGGCCGGGGCACGGCGGCGCACUGUCGCGCAGCUCGCGAGAAAGGGGCCCCUGCAGGGAAACCCCGCACUCUGCAUCCCUGCAUUUCCACAUUGUAGAGUAAAAGAUCAAGGCACGAACUAUAUAGAUUUACAGAAAAUAGGCCAAAGAUUGAGAUUUUUUUGACACAAGCAAGUCCAGAGAACUUUUACCAUGUAUGGUUACCGGCGCUUAAGAAGCCCCAGAGAUUCCCAGACAGAACCGCAGAAUGACAAUGAAGGAGAGACCAGUUUGGCUACCACACAAAUGAAUCCACCCAAACGUCGCCAAGUGGAGCAGGGUCCCAGUACAGGUGCAAAAAAACCCUCAAUUUCAGGAGCUCCACACCUGAAUUCAUACCAGUCCCUGGAACUUCCCCAGAAUCAGCAGGAUUCUGGCACUGAGGAGCUCAUGAUAGUCCUGGAACAAGGGACAGAAGUGAGGUUGAGCCUGGAAGAGGUCAUCCUCAUCUUGGCCCCAGAGACAGUGCUGCAGCUGACCCUGGAGAACACAGUCCUUGUGAUUGUCCCUGAGCAUGUCCUGAGGUCAGAAGAUGGCCUGCAGUCCCCUGUGCAGAUCCAGUACAUCAUACCUUCCGUUGAUGACUUCAGCUUGGAGUUCCAUGCUCAAGAUGGAGACAUCUCAGACAUGAGAAGAGAGAAUGUGCCUUUUUCACCUGCAGAAGAAGGGAAGGCAGCACCCCUGUAUCAGCAGCCCUUGAUGAUACCCCAAGCAAACCACAUGGCUGGGAUCAGCCCUUCUUUCCUAGUAACCCCAUUGUGCAUUCCACGCUGUCGGGCAGCCUUCCCCCAAUGCUACCCUCUACCACCCACACCUAGUCCUGUGGGACGCCCUAGACCAGCCGACUCCAGUUUCAGCCUGCAUGGUAUGGAGCUCUUGUGCACCUCCUCCCUCAGACCUAUGCCCCCUUCACCAAGUCCUGGUCCCCAGGUCUAUCACAGGGUUCACCAUAGGCCUCCCAGCAGGGCACGGAGAUGUCUCUUUAGGAAGUGAUUUAACCCAAGAGCCACCCCCUGCAUUGAUAGGUCAGAGAUUGUCCAGAUCCUUAGUCAGUGCAUUCUCUGAAAUGUGGAGAGAAAGUAAUUUGACCACUUGCUUGCCCUUUGCUGUUCCCCAUCAUCAACCACUGUCUUCAACAGCGGAGGGUCCCAGAUGCUGCAGGGAGGGGGAGAACUGCAGGGAGUUCAAAUAAAACAUUCACAUUUCACUUCACACACACUGUCCCUUAGACUUUCUCUUCCUAUUUAAGCACAUACAUCCAACCACACUCAAUCAAAUCCCUGACUGCUCCAUGUGAGAGUUCUGCUUCCAGCAUGACGUGGUCUGAAAGUUCAUCUGAAGACAGCUGCUCACUCCCGGGGGCUAACACCGCCCCUUGCAUGCUGAUGUCCUUGUAGUCAUUGGUCUGAUGCCACAAUAAAUAAUUCCUAAGGCUGAUGCUCUAUUUCUGCCCUGAGACUCUCCCCUUUUUCUCCAAGCUGUGCCCCAUUCCUUGUCUUAGUCCAGGUUCCCUACACUCCCCAGGCCAAUGCUUUUGAAUAAAUCUUGACGUCAUUGAAUGAA